GGAGGGAGACUGCUGGGGCCUUGCCGUCUCUCCGGAUGGGUUGCUCGUGGAGGAAGACCUUGUCUUUCUUCCUUGUUUUUGUGCCUAUAUAUCUACAUGGGGCUUCAUCGCAGGAAGCCGCCCCAGUGGGGCCCAGGAAACCGUUUUUCGAGAGGCUCCGUAGGCUGGAGGAACAGUUCCGGAGAUUCCAGGAGGUGACCUGGACACACCUGCAGAACAUCGCCAGCAACUACAACGUGUCCUACAACGUUGACGUCCGGUUCCGGAGCCUGGCGGAAGAGAGCCAGGCUGUGGCUCAGGCAGUCAACCGGUCACAGGCCUCGGUGCAGGGGGAGCUGGCGCAGCUCAAGGCCUGGGUGAGGAAGCUGCAGCGCCGAGGCCGGAAAGUAGACACGCGGCUGCGGGCCUUGGACCUCACCCUGGGCGAGAGGAGCCAGCAGCGGGCCCGGGAAAGGAAGGCACACAAGGCCCAGAGGGACGCCCUGCAGGACUCACUGGCACGCCUGGAGGGCCUCGUCCACAGCCAGGGCGCCAGGCUGGCUGCUCUGGAGGGGCGGCUGCCCGUGGCCCACCCUGGCACUGCAGCCCUCGGGCCGGCCCUGGUCCCAACCCCAACCCAGCCUGAGGAGCUGGGCCCGACCUCCCUGAAGCUUCAGAGGGACAGGCAGGAGCUCCGAGCUGCCUCUGAGCACAGGGGCCCCCCACAGGACUCCUCGGCCCCUCUCCAAGGGAGGCGGGAGCCUCCAGCCUCAGGCAGCCAUCGGGUACUCAGUGGGACUGCCCCAAAAGACCCUCGGCAGCAGGCAUGGUCCCCCCAGGUGCCAGGAGAGAUUUGCGGCGUGGGCCCCACCCUCGUUUUCCCAAACGCCUCCACCAGGAACGUGGUCUUCCUCAGCCCUGGUUUCGUCACUGCCCUGCGAGCCCUGUCCUUCUGCAGCUGGGUCCGCACGGCCUCCGGCCGCCUGGGCACCCUCCUGUCCUACGCCACCGAGGACAAUGACAACAAGCUGGUGCUGCACGGCCGAGACUCCCUGCUGCCCGGAUCCAUCCACUUCGUGAUCGGGGACCCGGCCUUCAGGGAGCUGCCCUUGCAGCUGCUGCUGGACGGCCAGUGGCACCACAUCUGUGUCAUCUGGACGUCCACCCAGGGCAGGUACUGGCUCCACGUGGAUCGCAGGCUGGUGGCCACCGGCUCCCGCUUCAGGGAGGGCUAUGAGAUCCCCCCCGGAGGGUCCCUCGUGCUGGGCCAGGAACAAGACAGCGUGGGGGGCGGAUUCGACAGCUCCGAGGCCUUCGUGGGGAGCAUGUCUGGCUUGGCUAUCUGGGAUCGGGCGCUGGUUCCCGGGGAAGUUGCAAACCUUGCCAUCGGGAAAGAGUUCCCGACAGGUGCCAUCCUGACGCUGGCCAAUGCUGCACUAGCAGGCGGAUUUGUGCAGGGGGCCAACUGCACCUGCCUGGAACGCUGUCCCUGAGGCCGAGCCGCACGGGGGCUGAGGCCAGCAAGGGCAGCAUGCCCCCAUCCACA